AGUUCCCAGCUGUCCGAAAGGUCUUCGGAACUUCGGCUCUAAAGCGUUCCUCAGCGCCAUCCGCCCGGAAACACGAGCGACAGAGAAAAGGUCCGCGAGGCCGGCAGACUCCAGAGUGGCUGGGUCCGAGCGCGGGGCGGGUUGCCGAAGGGCCUCGGCCUGGGCUGCGUGCUGGAGAGCGGGGACGGGGCCGACUCACCAGAGGCUGCAGCAACAGGUCCACUUUGCUCUCCAGUCUCUUUCUCCGACACCGCUGAGGCGGUUUCCCACCGACUUCCUUUCCAUACAGCACCGGCAGGCACCGGUGUGAAGGGUCAUAAAAAUGGCGCUGGCCGCUCGUUUGCUACCCCAGUUCCUGCACUCUCGGUCGCUGCCCUGCGGGGCCGUCCGACUCCGGACUCCUGCUGUGGCCGAGGUGAGGCUGCCGUCGGCCACACUUUGCUACUUCUGCCGCUGUCGCCUCGGCUUGGGAGCGGCGUUAUUUCCACGAAGCGCUAGGGCCUUGGCAGCCUCGGCGCUACCUGCCCAGGGCUCCCGGUGGCCAGUGCUCAGCAGCCCGGGACUCCCCGCAGCCUUCGCUUCUUUCCCUGCCUGCCCUCAGCGCAGCUACAGCACGGAGGAGAAGCCCCAGCAGCACCAGAAAACCAAGAUGAUCGUCCUGGGAUUCUCCAACCCCAUCAACUGGGUUAGGACUCGAAUUAAGGCCUUCCUUAUCUGGGCCUAUUUCGACAAAGAGUUCAGCAUCACAGAGUUCUCCGAGGGAGCGAAGCAGGCUUUUGCUCAUGUAUCCAAGUUGCUGUCACAGUGUAAAUUUGAUCUGUUGGAAGAACUUGUGGCCAAAGAGGUGCUACAUGCAUUGAAAGAAAAGGUUACUUCACUACCUGACAACCAUAAAAAUGCCCUUGCUGCUAACAUAGAUGAAAUUGUAUUUACAUCAACAGGAGACAUCUCCAUUUACUAUGAUGAGAAAGGAAGGAAGUUUGUUAACAUCCUGAUGUGCUUUUGGUAUCUAACCAGUGCCAACAUCCCCAGUGAAACUUUAAGAGGAGCCAGUGUAUUCCAGGUUAAGUUGGGGAAUCAGAAUGUGGAAACUAAACAACUUCUUAGUGCAAGCUAUGAGUUUCAGAGGGAGUUCACACAAGGAGUAAAGCCUGACUGGACCAUUGCACGGAUUGAACACUCAAAAUUAUUAGAAUAAUUUUCUUGGAAAAAUCAGCUUAUGGACUUUAGCAGUUGCUGUGAAAAACUAAGGAAGAAAAAUUUUGGGGUCAUUUGAUCUUCACUUAAUCUAAGUCUGUGAAUUACUUUUAUAUUAUUUUGAAAUACUCCUUGCAGUAUAUUGGCAUGAUACAGUAAAAGCAUUUUCCACAGAUUGUUAUCACCUUCUUUAAAAGAAGUCAAAAUUUAAAAAAUACAAUAGCACGUUGUUGGUGUCAUAUUCAAUAACAUUUCCAAUGCUACAUAUAAUUUUAUAGACAUAAUAAAGAAGGUAUUGAAAAAACUA